GCCAGCAUCAUUCAAUAGAAACAUAGAAUGUGAGCCGCACAUGCAAUUUUAGAUGUUCCAGUAGCUACAGUGAAAAAGUUAAAAUAAGCAAGUGAAUUUCUUCUUAGUGGUAAGUGUUAUUUAUCCAAUAUUAUCUUUUACACAUCAUCAAUAUAGAAAUUAUUAAUGAGAUAUUUUAUAUCCCCUUUUCAUAGUAAGUCUUCAAAACCUGGUGGAUAUUUUGCACUUACCACACAUCCCAAUUUGGACCACCCCUGUUUUAAUUGCUCUAUAGCUACAUGUAAGCUCUUUGAGGACAUACAUGAUAUCUGUUUUGUUUUCCAGUGCUUAGCAUAUGCCUGGUACCUGAUAUAUAUGUUUAAAUACUUGUUAAAUGAAUAAGUGGCUGAUGGACAUGGAUAGGUGUAUUAGUCAUCUAUUGGUGUGGCUAUCAUAUUAAGCAAUGUCAACAAAGAAAACUGAGGUUUUCCCAGUGUUCUGCAAAGUGCUAUUCAGGCAUAGCUGCAAGAUAAGCCUCCAACUCCCCACUUCCAACCAGAAUGGCUCCUGGAGUCCCUCUUCUGUAGAAGGGAGACUAGUGAAGCAGUGAUGGGGAGCGUGGCCUUGAGCCAGCUGCCUGGGCUUAAACCUAGCCUCGGCCACUUUCCAGCCACACUAUCUUAGGCAAGUUACCAAAUCUCUCUGUGUCUCACUUUUCUCUUCUGAAAAAUGAAGAUAAUUUAGUUCCUCUCAGAGUUUUGUGAGAAUUAAGUGCUUAGAAUACAGUAAGUACUUUAUAAAUGCAGUCUGUGUAUAGAAAUUUUAAAGUGGCCACUGUCGCCUGCUCUUUUAACAUAGAAAUCUGAUUCUCCCACUUCUUGGUUAAAACACUUCUAAGAUUUCACUGCAAGGACCUGACCCCUGUCUGCCUCUCCAGCCUCCUUUCAAGCCUCUUCCCUGGCUCCCUGCACUCCUGCCUCUGUUUUCACCUCAAGUCCUCCCCACUUGCUCAUCCUUUGCCUGGAGCCGACUUCUGUUAAUCCUGUCAGUUUUGCUAAAAUAUUAUUUCCUCAAGGAUUCCUUCCCUGGGCCUCCAGAUUAAAUUAAUUCCCCUUUAUAAACACUUAUAACAUGCUAUACAUUUCCGUUUCCUCUCAUUGCACUUAUCCCAGCUGAAAUUACUUAGUUUUAGGUAUGAUUAGUUGUUAAUGCCUGUGUCCUCAAACGCUUCUACCCUAUCGUAAGCUCUUUGAGGACAUACAUCAUAUCUGUUUUCUUUUCCAGUGCUUAGCAUAUGCCUGGUACCUAACACAUAUUUUAAAAUACUUAUCGAAUAAACAAAGGAAUGAAUACAUGGGUGAUGGACAUAGAUAGGAGUAUUAGUUAUCUGUUGCUGCAUAAUACAUUACUACAAACUUACCAGCUUAAAACCACACACAUAGAUUAUCUCACAAUUUCUAUGAGACGGAAAUCCAGGCAUGGCUUACCUGGGGCCUCCACUUAAGGCUCUCUCAAGAGGCUGCAAUCAAAGUGUUGGCAAAGGCUGGAGUCUAACAUAAAAGCCCAGCUAGAAAAGGAUUCACUUCCAAGUUCACGUGGCCGUCGGCAGGAUUCAGUUCCUUGUGGGCUGCUGGAGUAAGGGCUCAGUUUCUUGCUGGUUAUUGGCCAAAGCCUGCCUUCAGUUCUGUGCCAUGUGGGCCUCUCCAUAGGGCUGUUCACAACAUGUCAGCUUGCUUCAGAGCCAUCGAGGAAGAAAGUCUGCUAGCAAGAACAUUAUAAUUCUUUGUAAUGUCAUCAUGGAAGUGGCAUUCCAUUGUUUUCCAUAGUCUGUGGUUAGAAACAAAUCACUGGUCCUGCCUGCACCCAAGGGAAGGAGAGUACUCAAGGGCCUGAUCACCAAGGAGGCAGGAUCACUGGGGACCAUCCUAGAGUCUGUCUGCUACAGUAGUCAUGAGGACAGAUGAAAAGGUCCACUUAACUUGGUAGUUAAUUGGUAGUAUAUAGUAUACUCCUUGUGUAUGUAAUUUGCCCUUCAUCUGUUGUAUUUUCUGUGCAUUUUUAUUGUGCUCUAUGAGUCUUCUGCAACUCACAGGUAAUAGAUGUCACAGGCAGACUAAAAAUCAACCUUGAGAAUGUUUUAUAUACAGCUGUAAUUCUCAAUGCACUGUAACUGCCCCAGAAUCAUACCAUUUCUUCUCCUCUAAUAUCCCUUCUGCAUGUUUGGCAAUAUCUCUAAAAACUGGUUUUGGAACAUGAUGAACAUAUUUGGUACCAAAAAAGCUGAAUAUCACAAUGGAUGUUGUUUUCUUCUGGGCAAUGAAUUUGAUACUUGCACUAUUCUAUGUGAUUUCCCAUGUGGAAAUCUUUUCAGAAGCCAGAUAGAUUUUUCAAAGCAUACAUUUAUCACCAUGCUUUGAUGGGAUGAAAUAAGUUUCACUGACAUUUCAAAUUAGCAUUUCUUUUCCUAAUCUUAUCCCAUUCUUCUUAAAUGCAGUGAUUUAUGAAGCAAUAUUACAUAUGCUUCUCCCAACCUUUCCAUAAUGUAUACCCCUUUCAAAUGCUGGUAGAUGGGUAUUUCUUUAGCCAAAUUGGACCAUUCUGUUUUACUCCUCUCUCAGAAAUUGUUCCUCCUGAGUAAUUUUAUUAAUUUUCUAUCCUCCCUCCAGUUUUGCUUCUGGUUCCAUGAUUUGUAAUAUAAUAAGACGCUAGGACAAAAAAUAAAUGUAGACAUGCACUAAAAAGAAAAUAAUUACCUAAAAAACAUUAGAAUAUUUCAAUCUGUUGUCAAGCGAUACAUAAGAAAGCUACUGAUCGUCACCAAGACCAGACUAAAGCUAAGUAUUUUUUCUUUCCAAUCCCACAGUCUCCCACCUCCAAUUUUUGGCAACCUUCCUUUGAGAGUCAACACUGCUUGGCUAUUCAUUAAUGGAAAACUCACGCUUAUUACCCAAGUUCACAAAAAAUUGUGAUUCUGUAUGUAAUGGUCUUGUUUGUGGCAGUGUUUGAUUAUUUGCUUGAAUAAGCCCUUCUUUAGGAAUUUACAUAACCCAAAAUGUAAAUGCUGAUUUUUCACGGGUGUCUAUAAAGCAAUUGGCCUUGAUAACAUUCAGCCUUUCUAGAUUAUAUUCAUCAUCCUCUUUUUUGAAAGCAAGGACUGUAUUUUCAUCUUUAUGAUUUUCUCUUCUCCUAAUAACCAUGUGCCUCUCCCCAAACCUCAUGAGCCACCCUGGUGCCUCUGCCCCAGGCCUCCUCAGCCCAGCCCUUCCUUCACUCUAGUGUAGCAGGGGCUCAGGCACCAAGAGGGUAUGUUCUGCAUUGGAAGGCACACAGCUGUGAAGCCAGAUCAGGUUUCAGCUCUACCAUUUCAUUAAUUCCUUCCUUCCUUUCUAUUGUUUACACAGCACCUGCUAUGUACUAGGUGCUAGGGUCUAUGUGGGAUAUACUGUGUGGCUUAACCCAGCUUCUUCCUCUGUAGAAUAGGUGAAAAUGAGGAAAUUGUUGAGAUCAGAGAUCAUGUAUGUGAAGCACCCAGUAGCAUGUCUGGGACCCAGCAGGGCUCGGCAAAUGGCAGCUAAAGCUCCUCCUAACUGUGCUUUCCCCUGCUAUGUCAUGCUCCUGUCGUGUCCGACACUUACAGAUCCUGCUCUCUGUUUCUAGAGCCACUGGAUACUUCUUGUUCCCCUUUCCCCUUCAUUUCUGAUCAGACUAGAAAAAUAAGUCAUACUGCAUGUACUGAAUAGCCAUGGAUGUGGAGAAAUGUACUACUACUCUUGAGAUAAUAUUUGAUUCAAAAGAUCUCUCUCUGAGGUCAGGUCAUAGACCUUAGCAACAAUGCUCUGAUUACCAUCCUACCAAUGAUGAUCAUAGCUCUAGAAUUUCCCCAUCUAGUGGUUGACUUGGCUGAUAAUAACUGGCAGUGUGAUGAUAGUGUGGCAGUCUUUCAAAAUUUUAUUUCUGAAUCCUGGAGGAAAAAGUGGAAUGUCAUUUGCAACAGGUCUAUAGGGAGUGAGGAGGCCAACGGGGGCACUCCCCAGAGCAGGAUUUCCAGGGAAACCCGCCUUCCUCCCAUUCAUCUGCAUCGCAUGAAAAGCCUCAUAAGGAGCAAAGCAGAGAGGCCCCAGGGAGGAAGGCACACGGGCAUUUCUACUCUGGGGAAGAAGGCAAAGGCCGGCUCUGGUCUCAGGAAGAAGCAGAGACGGCUGCCAAGGAGUGUUAGAAGCACCCGCGAUGUGCAGGCUGCCGGCAAAAAAGAGGACGCUCCCCAGGACCUGGCUCUGGCGGUGUGCCUGUCAGUGUUCAUCACAUUCCUUGUCGCCUUCAGCCUGGGGGCUUUCACAAGGCCUUAUGUUGACAGACUGUGGCAAAAAAAGUGCCAGAGCAAAAGCCCUGGCCUGGACAACGCGUAUUCAAACGAGGGCUUCUACGAUGACAUGGAAGCUGCGGGGCACACACCACACCCAGAGACCCAUCUGCGCCAAGUAUUUCCUCAUCUAAGCCUCUACGAGAACCAGACCCCUUUCUGGGUGACACAGCCACACCCACACGCCACCGUAAUUCCUGAUAGAACUCUGGGAAGGAGCAGAAAGGAUCCUGGCAGUUCGCAGAGCCCAGGACAGUGCGGGGACAACACCGGGGCAGGAAGUGGAAAUGAUGGUGCAGUCUAUUCCAUUCUCCAGAGACAUCCACAUGCCGGUAACCGUGAACUAAUGUCAGCAGCGCAGGACCACAUCCAUAGGAAUGAUAUUCUCGGAGAAUGGACUUAUGAAACUGUGGCCCAGGAAGAGCCUCUCAGUGCACAUUCAGUGGGCGUCUCUUCUGUAGCUGGCACGUCUCACGCUGUCUCUGGCUCAAGCCGUUAUGAUUCCAAUGAAUUAGACCCUUCCCUCUCCGGAGAAAUAACAGCUUCCCUCUGUAAAAUGCUAACACAUGCAGAAGCACAGAGGACUGGAGAUAGUAAGGAAAGAGGGGGCACUGAACAGUCACUUUGGGACUCGCAGAUGGAAUUUUCUAAGGAAAGGCAAGUGAGUUCAUCCAUUGAUUUGCUGAGCAUACAGCAGCCAAGGCUGUCCGGGGCAAGGGCUGAGGAAGCGCUUUCAGCCCACUACAGCGAGGUUCCAUACGGUGACCCAAGAGACACAGGCCCAUCAGUCUUUCCUCCAAGAUGGGACAGUGGCCUGGAUGUCACUCCUGCUAACAAGGAACCAGUGCAGAAAUCCACUCCUUCUGACACUUGCUGUGAGUUGGAGAGUGACUGUGACUCUGAUGAGGGGUCUCUGUUCACUCUGAGCUCCAUAAGUUCAGAGAGUGCAAGGAGCAAGACUGAAGAGGCAGUGCCUGAUGAGGAGUCCCUGCAGGACGAGAGCUCAGGGGCAAGCAAGGACAAUGUGACGGCUGUAGACAGUCUUGAGGAAAAUGUUACCUUCCAAACAAUUCCAGGGAAAUGCAAGAAUCAAGAAGAUCCCUUUGAAAAACCUCUCAUUUCUGCUCCAGACUCUGGCAUGUACAAGACUCAUCUGGAAAAUGCCUCUGACACUGAUAGAUCUGAGGGCCUGUCACCCUGGCCCAGGUCACCAGGGAAUAGUCCCUUAGGGGAUGAGUUUCCGGGCAUGUUCACUUAUGAUUAUGACACAGCUCUUCAAUCCAAGGCAGCAGAAUGGCAUUGCUCACUUAGAGACUUAGAAUUUUCAAAUGUGGACGUUUUACAGCAAACACCACCAUGUUCUGCUGAAGUUCCCUCAGAUCCUGAUAAGGCUGCCUUCCAUGAAAGAGACUCAGACAUUUUAAAAUAAGAAUCUUUCAUUAAGGAAAUAUUCACAGCUCUAAACAAUAUUCUUUUAAAGAUCAUGGCAGGGGAAAACUAAAGCCUUCACAACAAGAUCCUGAAGGAGACAACAUGAAUUCCAACCAAGUGGACACUGAUGCAAAUGAGGGUUUUGUGGGCCCACUUGAGGGCGAUGAUUCUAGAAGGGUUAUAAGCUAAACACACUUGUUAACAUCCUAUGGGGAUGAACCUGCUCUUCAGUGUGAAAGAGAAAGAGGGGAAUAUUUUGAGAUCAUUCCAAGAACCAUGCACCAUUAUUACAAGAGCUCCAAACAAAACCAGUUCACUGAGAACACAGGAGCACUUCAUCAAUAGGUUGGGGUAAAUAUUCAGAAGAGAAUCUGUUGCAGUUAGACGAAGUGGUUCUAACUUUCCUUCUCAAAUACAGACCUGGAGCAAUCUGAUGGGAUUUGGCUCUCUGAAAAGAACAGCUUUAGGAUGACAAAGACAAGGAUGUUCAACUUGAUCAUCAAAGAGAAUUCAAAUGACAUUUUUUCAUACAUAUUGAAGCACUUAAGUGGAAAUGCUGGAUAGAUUUUAAUGAAUUCUGAACACACACUAGCACAACUUUUUGGAGGCUGAUCGUGAAACUGCAAAAUUGGAAAAGUUCUGAGUAAAUAUAAAUGUUUUUAAAUAAGUUAUGUUAAAAGAGAAGAGGGGCCACUUUUUAGAAUAAAGUGUAAAUUAAAAAUCAA